ACUCUCCUUGCACAGCUCAGCAGGACCUCAGCCAUGAGACUUCUCAUCCUGGCCCUCCUUGGCAUCUGCUCUCUCACUGCAUACAUUGUGGAAGGUGUAGGGAGUGAAGUCUCAGAUAAGAGGACCUGUGUGAGCCUCACUACCCAGCGACUGCCGGUUAGCAGAAUCAAGACCUACACCAUCACGGAAGGCUCCUUGAGAGCAGUAAUUUUUAUUACCAAACGUGGCCUAAAAGUCUGUGCUGAUCCACAAGCCACAUGGGUGAGAGACGUGGUCAGGAGCAUGGACAGGAAAUCCAACACCAGAAAUAACAUGAUCCAGACCAAGCCAACAGGAACCCAGCAAUCGACCAAUACAGCUGUGACUCUGACUGGCUAGUAGUCUCUGGCACCCUGUCCGUCUCCAGCCAGCCAGCUCAUUUCACUUUACACGCUCAUGGACUGAGUUUAUACUCACCUUUUAUGAAAGCACUGCAUGAAUAAAAUUAUUCCUUUGUAUUUUUACUUUUAAAUGUCUUCUGUAUUCACUUAUAUGUUCUAAUUAAUAAAUUAUUUAUUAUUAAGAAUAGUUCCCUAGUCUAUUCAUUAUAUUUAGGGAAAGGUAGUGUAUCAUUGUUGUUUGAUUUCUGACCUUGUACCUCUCUUUGAUGGUAACCAUAAUGGAAGAGAUUCUGGCUAGUGUCUAUCAGAGGUGAAAGCUAUAUCAAUCUCUCUUAGAGUCCAGCUUGUAAUGGUUCUUUACACAUCAGUCACAAGUUACAGCUGUGACAAUGGCAACAAUUUGAGAUGUAUUUCAACUUGUCUCUAUAAUAGAAUUCUGUUUAUAGAAUAAGGGAGAAAAUAAUCCAGUCUUCACUGGGUUCCCAUUCUGAGGGUCCACUACUCAAAAAUUUGCUUCACUCAAUUUUUUUCACCUCUUUGUGUUUUAUUUUGGUGUCCUAUUAAAGGAAUAAAAUGACACAACUUGUCCCUUUUUUGUCCCAUUAGCAAAAAUUAGAAUUUUGGUAUAAAGAAACUUUAUUCAAGUAAAAAUCAAUACCCUUUGAAUUGGACAAUAAUCUCACUACCUUAUUAGGAUUUCUGUAUUUGCCAUUACGCUAGUUAUCAUGCAUGUUAUGCUUUACUGCGAAUAAGCUUUUAAUGCUCCAAAUGCUGACCCAUGCAAUAUUUCCUCAUGUGAUCACAAUUUGCAGUAAACUUUUAAUUAAAUGCUCAUCUGGUAACUCAA